GGCCGUGUGUCGCUUCCCGGCUGUGCACCCUCCGGGGCCGCCGGCUCUCGGGGGACGCGCUGGGGAUGGGGCCAGACGCCCCGGUCGCGCGCCCCCCUCCUUCGCGGAGCUGCCCGGUUCGCCAGCCCCCGCGGAAACGCCUCGGAGCGCGGUAGCCAUGGGGACCAGGGCGAAGGUUAACCGAGUAUUUGAAUAGCGAGGAAAAGGGAGGCCGGGGCGAGCCUGGCGUUCGCUCGCGCUCUCUUGCUUAAUGGCAAAUUGUGGGCGAGCGCUGCGUUUAAGGAAGUGCUGCUUUGAAAGCUGUUGCGCAGCCAUUGGUACCUGUAUUGGGGAAACAUAGCAUACAAGCAAGAAGCUUACAGCCUCAGUGGCGAAAAUUUUUUCAUGUCAGAGACCGAGAACUCUUGCAGUCGUUUAUGUCAUCCCUUCUUCUCCAGACAGAAGAUACCAAAAAGUUGCAAUCAAAGAUCUCUUCAUCUUAUUGAUAAAGCCACUAAUAAGCCAAAAUGUCUGUCAAUGUCAACCGCAGCGUGUCAGACCAGUUCUAUCGCUACAAGAUGCCCCGUCUGAUUGCCAAGGUUGAGGGCAAAGGCAAUGGAAUCAAGACAGUUAUAGUCAACAUGGUUGACGUUGCAAAGGCGCUUAAUCGGCCUCCAACGUAUCCCACCAAAUAUUUUGGUUGUGAGCUGGGAGCACAGACCCAGUUUGAUGUUAAGAAUGACCGUUACAUUGUCAAUGGAUCUCAUGAGGCGAAUAAGCUGCAAGACAUGUUGGAUGGAUUCAUUAAAAAAUUUGUUCUCUGUCCUGAAUGUGAGAAUCCUGAAACAGAUUUGCAUGUCAAUCCAAAGAAGCAAACAAUAGGUAAUUCUUGUAAAGCCUGUGGCUAUCGAGGCAUGCUUGACACACAUCAUAAACUCUGCACAUUCAUUCUCAAAAACCCACCUGAGAAUAGUGACAGUGGUACAGGAAAGAAAGAAAAAGAAAAGAAAAACAGAAAGGGCAAAGACAAGGAAAAUGGCUCCGUAUCCAGCAGUGAGACACCACCACCACCACCACCACCAAAUGAAAUUAAUCCUCCUCCACAUACAAUGGAAGAAGAGGAGGAUGAUGACUGGGGAGAAGAUACAACUGAGGAAGCUCAAAGGCGUCGAAUGGAUGAAAUCAGUGACCAUGCAAAAGUUCUGACACUCAGUGAUGAUUUGGAAAGAACAAUUGAGGAGAGGGUCAAUAUCCUCUUUGAUUUUGUUAAGAAAAAGAAAGAAGAGGGUGUUAUUGAUUCAUCUGACAAAGAAAUCGUUGCUGAAGCAGAAAGACUGGAUGUAAAAGCCAUGGGCCCUCUUGUUCUAACUGAAGUUCUUUUUAAUGAGAAGAUUAGAGAACAGAUUAAGAAAUACAGGCGCCAUUUCCUACGAUUUUGUCACAACAACAAAAAAGCCCAACGGUACCUUCUUCAUGGUUUGGAGUGUGUGGUAGCAAUGCAUCAAGCUCAGCUUAUCUCCAAGAUUCCACAUAUCUUGAAGGAGAUGUACGAUGCAGACCUUUUAGAAGAAGAGGUCAUCAUCAGCUGGUCGGAAAAGGCCUCUAAGAAAUAUGUCUCCAAAGAACUUGCCAAAGAGAUUCGUGUCAAAGCAGAACCAUUUAUAAAAUGGUUGAAGGAGGCAGAGGAAGAAUCUUCUGGUGGCGAAGAAGAAGAUGAAGAUGAGAACAUUGAGGUGGUGUAUUCGAAGGCUGCCAGUGUACCGAAAGUUGAGACUGUAAAGUCAGACAACAAGGAUGACGACAUCGAUAUUGAUGCCAUUUAAAGGGAUGGAUGCAACCUAGCUUAACAGUAUAAUGCUGCAAAUUUUCCUCCAUUAUCAGCCAGAAGUGCAACAUGUAUGUGCAAAAGCUAAAAUGGCUUAACAUCAUGCUACACUUUACACUAAAAAUCUAUUACUGUGAGUGGUCUGUUAUUAAGCCCAAUGAGACAUCUAGGGAGUCCAUACACAUCAGUGAGCAGAUGUAGUUUGCUUAUUUAUAGCAUGUUUCUUUUUGAAAAACUAGUGGUGGACACAUUUGGAUCACAUUUAUACAGUUAUAAAAAUAAAGGUUUGAUUUUGGUCGUUCUUCAGAUGUUUGGCUCUGAAUGACUUAAGCUGAAGUAACUGGCUCCUUACUUUAAAUGUUCUGCCAUCAUUUCACCUGAUGAGCAUUCUUGGAGCCUGCCAGAUAUUGUUAGGUCCUGGGGCUGCAAAGAGGUCCUCAACAGGAUGUAAAGCAAACUUAAUUGUAAUUAAUUUAUUCAGCCCAUUAAGAAAGUACUAAAGUUUUAUCUCUGUAGUUCCUCAAAUUGGCAUCUGGUAAUGUACAUUGUGAGGUAGACUGAUAAUGAAAUGACAGUGUAACAUCUUAACCAAGAAGUAAAUAUGACCUCAGUGUCCUAUAAAUAAUGUAAGAGCAGGAUUUGAAACUUGGAGAGCUGUUUUCUCAUUUCAUGUACACUUGCCCCAAAUUGUCUUUGAAGUCGUGUGCAUUGCACGUUGGAUGAGCCAGGGAAAUUAUUACAUUAACAAGCAUUUUGUGUGUACGUAGUAGUUACUUUGUACUGAGAGAACUUGCUUUGGGGUGCAAUUAAUAAACUGAUUUUAUUUGGGAGAAACAAGGAAGGGUGCACUUAACUAGCAACCUAAGCAUGAUUUUUCAGCUUUUGCCCUUAGGGUUUAAAUUACAAUUCCAAAAUGUUAGACAUACUGUAUUUUUUCGUUCAGUGUGGCUUUAAUUUUCCCCUCUUGCAGUUUGUUCUGUAAUGCCUUUUACAUUUGGACACAUAGUUUAUGCUUUUUAGAUUUUGGUUGCUUUCUUGCCAAAAUAAGUGUUAACUGUGUUUCAAACUUGAUUUUCUUUCCUUUUUCUUUUUUUUUUCUUCCAGAAUGUCUUAUUUAAAAAGAAAGCUAAAAGCAUACUUCUAAGUCAGAGCCUCUAUUUUGGUGUAAGACUUGGGAUAUUUUUUACUUCACAUUGAAUAUAGCCAGGCACCCAAGAAGUCUGAUGGCCACCUGAGUGCAGGUGACAAGGACCUGACAGAGCCCAUGCAGGGCUUUAGAUUUGGACACACAAGAGUUGAUAACUUCCUCAUGAACUCCUUGCCUGAUCUAAACUCAUAUUAUGGGUUCUGACUGUUUGAGUAAUCAUCUUCAAGGUUAAACCUCUUGGCAGUUACCCUUUUCACAAAGUGCACAGUGGGAAUCGAGAAUCGAUAGGGUUAAUUUUGGAGCAGUGGCUUAUACCAUUCACCUCUGUUUUUUUGUGAUUAUUUCACAGAUAAUGAGACCUUAAUAACAAAUAGGCGUAAAAAAAUUUUCACAUUGAAAUGAUAGAAACAUUUGAUGUAAUAAAACUUGGUUGGCUUGAUAUUUUAAGGAAUUGAAACCUAGCAAUCUUAUUGGAGAGACAAGAAUUGGUCUCCAGCUGCCUUUGAUCAAGAUUCGGGUGCAAGUGGAGCAGGAGCCAUAUACCUGGAGGGAAUGUGCUUUGUCACACCAAAGAGGAUUUUUUUUUCUUCAAACUUGUAUGUUGCCUAGGUUUCAAAUUCUUUGCCGCAAGGCUGAUCUGCUUUCAUUAACUGGAAUUCUGUAGGAGAUACUGGUGACCUAAGCUAAGUUGCACUCAGCAUACUCAGUGUCAAGCUAAUGAGGUUCUAUUAUAAAGGUUCUACUUUUAAUCUGAGGGAAAACAUGUUCAGGGCUUCUAGAACACUAAAAAAUUUGGCUUAAACCAGUGUUCAGUCUGGUGCCAAACUUCGAAUGGAAUACAAAUUCACAUAAUCUGAACUUUGUUCACAGGUUAUCCUAAUAGAGUAAUUCUUCACUUUGCUCUAUUGAACUGUCUUAAGGAUUUGUUUAAACAGCUAAGUUACUUGAUUAAAAUAAUGAUAAAAUUGUAUUUUGUCUUUGCUUUAAUAUUAAAGUUAACAAGUUUUCAUUUUAUAAUGAGAUCAAAGCAUUGGAAUCUGCCCUGUUUUGUAGCCGUUGCUUUGGAUUUGUGUUGGAUGUAUCCUGCAGUUACACUUGCCAGCCCCACUCACAAAAGUUGUUCAUUUCAUUGGGUCACUGGCUUUAUUUGCUAGUCUUGUCUGUGAACUGAGCAUCUGCCUCAGUUUUAUUACUUGAAAUCUUGGCAGGUGCUUAAUAGGGAACAUACAUACAGCUAUGUAACUGUGAAUAAUUGUAUAUAUCUCUAGUUAAGAAUGAGGGAAUGGGGAGGUUUGCUUUCUAAACAAGUGCAUUCUGAAAUUGACUUAAAAAUUUUUAGUGUGGGUCCUAAAGUUUAGAGAUGGGCAAGGAGGUCUCUAAUCCACCGCUUCCCGCUUGAGAAGGGAGGGGUAUCAAAAUUGAGCCCCAAGCUGUUUGUUCCAGUGUACCAAGCACUGACUUUAUGCCUUUGGCCUGGAGAUGGCAGAAGUGAAAGCUGGCCAUCUGCAAAAAGCAGAUAAGUGAGUUUGAACCUUUUGCAUUUUGUUAGCUCAGUCAGUCCUCAUCGUGGUCCUGAGGCAUAGGUACUGUUGUACCAAGGUCACUUAUCUAACAAAAUAACCCUUCAUGUAUUUUAAAUUUAUUUGACAAGUCUGCAGACAAUCCUUAUCUAACCAGCUAUUUUCUUAAUUGCUACAGCUUGACCUACCAGUAUUCCGGAGUAACCAGCAAAUGCAAAGUUGACCUUGUUCCUGCAUCAUCUUUUUGAUGGUUCAAAUUUCAGCCUCCCUGACUACUACAAAGCCAGAGCAGUCUUAGUACCAGAAACAGUGUUGCACUUUCGUUGCAUGUGCUGUGUGACCCCAAGGGGACAGGGAGUCACUUUGGUCAUCUCUGUCCCCAGUACAGAUCUUGAUUCAUAGUGACAUUCCAUAAGUGGGGUGACAGCAAAUGACUUGCAGGUAGUCUCAUUGUAGGUUUGUGCACCAGAGUGACCCUGUGAGCCUUUGUUAAUAGGUUGGGAGCUCAGGGUGUUUAUGUCCACCUGUCUGGUCUAGCCAAACAGUUUUUUUCUGGGAAUCAAAUUUCUGUGGUUUUUAUGGCCAGAAAUUUUAAGGACUUGUGUGUGCUGGGAUAUGAGAAUAGAAGCUACAGAGUUCUUUUCUUGGGACCUAGACUGGGAGGUGCAAUGUCAGGACCUCCAGGUGAAUGGUAGGAUCUGAGUUGACCCUGCAGUUCGGUUAUGCAGUCAAUUAUUUCUUUUUAAGAGGAGGAGGAUUCACUUGGGUGUUGGGAUCAAAUUUGGAUUCUGUCCCAGGCCUUACUGUAAAACUAGGGGAUUGCCUUUCCAUAUCUGCUGGGGGUGGAGACCCUUAUGUGCAGCACUCAAUCCCACUGGAAGCCUAAUGCUGCAGUCAGAAGCAAUGCCUGGCUGGGGCAGUAGGGGAAAUUCCACCCAAUUUUGCUAUGAGCCUAAAACCUCUUUAAAAACGGUCAGUUAACUAAAAAAUAAAAAUCAAGUCUUUAGGAGAGUAGAAAACACAAUUAACUAAAAAGCAGGGACAUCUGAAAGAGACGUAUUAAGUUAACAUUUUUAAAAAUCCAAAUGAAAGUAAAUGGAAUAAAUGUAUCAGGUAAAGGACAAGUUGUAAGCUUGGAUUUUUAGGUCUAGCAAUACACUGUUUACAAGAGCAUCACCUAAAAUGUGACAAAAGAUGUUGAAAGGAUGAAAAAAGGUAUAGUAGACAUACACUAACCAAAAAUGUAGCUCUUUGAAUCUCAGAAAAAAGUAGAUUUUAAUAAAGUGUGAAAGUUGUCAAUCAAA